UUGUUGCCUUUCAUUCUUUUAAUAUGUGAUUUGCAUACUUUAUAUUCAGAAAAACAUUACAGUUUUGAGUUGUCUGUAGUGAUUAGAAUAAAACUAAACCAGCAUUUCCCAAAUAGUAUUUAAAAAAUUACCAGGUCUUUGAACUGUCAUUUCUUGAAUAAAGAAUUCUUUAAGUCUGGGAAUCUUGAUGAUAAACUAUAUCAAGACUAUUUUCUUGGGUAUUCAGAAUGACUGUUAAUAUAUUCCAGGUCUAGCAUUUCUCAUUCCUUAUUAGGGAAGAGCUAAGAGAUCAUGAGAGGAAGAGUUGAAAUGUUGGUAAGUUACAGGUACUUUUGCAUGUGCUUUUGUAUAUGCAUAGAAAAAAAAGAACCUCAGACAGUUAUUACCUCUUGGUUUAAAUUUGGGAAAAACGUGGACUUUUGCCCUUUACACUGUGUAGUUAUGUAUAUUUUGCAUUCUUUUCCUUAUAGCAGGCCUUAACUUUUGAAAUAAAAGAACAUACAAUUGUAAAGCAUUCCAUCUUUUUUUUUUUUUAAUCAAGCCAUAAAGCCAGAUAAAAAUAUAAGAGCAUUUAUCACAUUUCUAGAUGGUGGAAGAUAUCCAAAGUUUAAUAGGUAUAUAAGAAAUUAGAAAGACAGAUUUUACUGUGUGAAAAGUUUAAAUUUUUGAAUAUUAACAGAAAAAAAGAAAAACAUUAACAGCAAAUAACUUGGGAAAAAUAUUUGUGGUAAAUAGGGCCAAGUCUUACUACUUUUAUAUAAAAGAGAUAUAUAAAUUGCCAAUAAGCACACAGAGAUUCCAGUAGAUAAAUAGGGAAAGUAGUCUCAUUAAAGGAAAUACUGUAACUAACAAACUCAAGAGAAAGUAUUUAGACCCAGUAGUAACCCAAAUAAAAUAAACGUUAAAUAAAAUAAACCCAAAUAAAAUAAACAUUAAAUAUAACCAUUUUUAUUUUUUAAUAAUUAAAGAAUUAUUACUGCUCGCAGAGGUAUAAUAAAAGUUGUGUUGCACACUUCUGAUACACAAAGGUGUGAUAAUAGGGAGCUGGUUAACAAGUUAACUGUGGUACAUCCUUCUCUUAUAGUGAUAUGUAGUCAUUAUGUCUCAGAAAAAUGUAUAAACUUAAGAACUUGACCAUAUUAUAAUGCCAAGUGAAGAAACAAGUCACACAAAAUUAUAUAUGUAAUAUGACCAUGACUGUAUAAAACAAAACAACGCAAGUCAUCUAAAGACAAAAUCUAGAGCAAUACAGUACAAAUAUUUAUAGUAAUUGUUCCUGAAUGGUAGAACUGUAGUGAUUCUUCUGCUUUUCAACUCUUAAAUUUUCAACUAGUUAGAUUUUCUUGAUGCUAUAGCCACUUGUUUUUGUAACAAGUAUAGUGCUAACUGAGGUAUUCGGUUUUGGAAAUCUUUAAAGUACAGACUUUUUUGAUGAUGGGAUUCAAUUUAACUUGUUUAUUUUUCAAUAAAAAUAUUUAGUGCAAAAAUUUUUGACACAUAAAUAUAGUGCAAAAUGAUAGGAACAUCAUGAUGUAUUUAGAAAUUUUAAAUUCAGUUUUAUGGGUAAAACUGAAAAAAGAAUUUUUUUGCAUUCUAAGUGAUAAUUUUGUGAUUCUUUUGAAGAACUGUUGUAAUCAAUGACUAAAAUUAGAUUUACUGGUGCAUUUUAAACUACUAUGUUUGUUUUAUUGCUUAAUUUAGACAUGUUCCUAUAAAUAAAAAGCAGUAAUCAGAAACAACAAUUUAACUCCAUUAAUUUAUGUUCCUGUGGGCAUGGUAGAGAAAUAACUUCUCUUGAAACAGUGAAAAUUCUAUUUUCUUUAUUUCAGUUCACUAAUACCAUUACAUGUUUAUAGUGUUUUGGAAUAGUAUUUUGAGACCCACUUUUUGUGUUCCAGAAAAGUUUUAAGAAACAGUUUCUUUCUUUUCUGAUUCUAAAACUGCAAGAGACACCAGUUAACUAAGUAGUCCUGACAAUGCGUGAACUUUGCUGUGUUUGACUCUAUGUGUUAAGGCAGAGAACUAAAUAAAAAACAUACUCUCUUUCUUAAUUUGGGCAUUCUUUUACUAUAUUGAAAGUUUUAGGUUUCAGUGGCUGGCCUCAAUAAAAUGUGCAUUGCUUUAGAGCAGUUCGAAUAAUAGUUAAAGAUACAGGCUUUGGUGUCAGAUAGACCUGAAAUUAAAUGUUGGCUGUGCCACUUUUCAGCUAUAUGACUUCUUUCAAGUUAUUUAAUACCACCAAAAACUUUCCUCAUCUGUAGAGUAGGAUAACAGUAGUAAUCAUCUCAUAAGAUUAAAUGAGAUCAUUCAUAUUUAAUGCUUAGGUAAGCACCUAGCUUAUGGGAUAAUUAAUAAAGGACAACUGUUAUUAUCAGUAAUUUUUUUCACCAAGUGUUUACUUCAUUUCUAAGCUUUUAAGUAAUUUUUAAAUAUAUACAUAUAUAUCUACUUGAUAUUUUACUUCUUUGCCAGAGUCUAACUUCUAGUAACUGCUACCUAAAAUCUCUUAUAUGAAAAUAGUUCUGCAGAUUAAAGUCAGCCUGUUGUGUAUUUGUGUGCUUGACUGUUCUAGUUAUGUUACUUAGUCUAGUGAGUUUCUUGGUUUUUCUGCAGAACCCAUUUGUACAAUGGGAAUAAAAAUAACUUCUUUCAUUGUUAAGAGGAUUAUGUGAAUUCAUAUUCUUAAAACCUGAAAAAUAGUGGUUAUAUAAGGUUUUGAGGAAAGUAAAGUUUGGUUUUGACAGUGGUAUCUUCAUUGUCAUCUGUGCCAUUAUAAACCCUUCUGUAGUUUGAGACACUGUUCUAAGCAUUUUUUAAUACGUAUUUAAUCCCUUUAGCAACCCUAUGAGGUAGUUAGGUAUAACUGUUUUACAAACUGCUGCACAGAGAGGCAGAGUAACUCACCCAUAGUCACACGCGAAUAAGUUGUACAGCUAGGAUUCAGACAUAAGUGUUGUAGCUCUAAAGUCUGUGCUAUUAAUCAGUAAUAUACUGUCUCAACCCUGUUUAUGCUCCAUCCAGCUACUACUUUGGGGUUUAUCUGGGAGUAGAGAAUGGAAAAAGGAGAAAUGAUCUGGAGUGGUUUCUAAUAGUCCUGAAGAAUAGAGGCAGUAUAAUUACUGAGGCCAGUGGUUAAUCAUCCUCUUCUCACUUAGUUAUAGAAAUACUAUUGUCUCUCGUUUCUCUUCUGUAAAUCUUACAAGUUCAUCACAGGAGUUUUUCUAGAGUAUCUUAACUUCCCUGUAUUAUGUGACAGCAUCUUAACCUCAGACUGCAUAUCCUUUUCCACUAUGCUCCAUCUGAGAACACAGUUCAGAUGCCUCAUGAUCUUUCCUAGUUUCCACCUAGUGUUGUUUCUAGCAUCCUUCUAUAGAUGUUGGGAGUCAGUCUAUAACAAUGGUGGCAGUCUUAUUAAGUGACUCUGUACCUCAAAGAUCAUUUAUUCUUUGGUGAAUGAAUUUUCCAUUUUAGAAAUCUUAGAUUCCAUUGUAUAUUACAUUAUCUCUUCAUAUUAGUUACACAGACCAGUGGACCAGACUAGUUGAAGGUUGUCUGGACAUUUUAUUUUAUGGCUUGGAAAUUUUAGUGAAAUUAAUGAAGGAAACUUCCAGGGAUAAGUCAGAAAUAAUUUGUGUUUAGCUUUAAAAUGUGUUCAUAUGCUUAUGUUUAAAUAGAAGUUUAGUAGAUUUCUAAAUUGCACAUCAUGUUUAAUUUCAGCAUAAUGAAAAAAAUUUAAACAAAUAUGUCAUCAUCAUGUAUACUUUGUUGAGAGCAGAGAUUUUUUUCCCCCUUCUUCCUGUCUUUUCACUGCUACUAUUACCCUCUUUUUUGUUAGAGACUAGCAUUUUUGAGGCUGAGUUUCUUUAAAAAAAAAAAAAGUUUCUGUACUGAAAUUCAGUACAUUUAAUUAUUAUAUAGUAAAGAUACUGGUCUUUUUCACUGAAGAAAAAAAGUCACUCCAAAAUAUAAUCAAAUCUCCUUCUCCUCUUCCCCCUCCACCCUCCCCAUAUAAUUUCAUCAGAUGGCAAUACUUCUUACCAGCUCACUGCUAAUGAAUUAGUGCCAGCUGGAAAGGAAGAAGAGCAUAGCUACCUGAGGUUAGCAAUUUUUAACUUCAACACAACUUGCCCCUUCUAAAAUCCAGCUUCUUUGCAGAAGAAACCUACAGUAAGGGACAGAAGCAUCUAAAUCGUAUCAAAUUUAAAGGUGACAAGAGAUCUGAAUUAGUUACAGACUCAUGAAAGUUUCCCUCAAUAUAUGUUUCUUUUUGCUAAUAUGUUGUGAGUGUUCUUUUUCUAGAGAGGAACUUUAGCCACUUUUUCCCCGUAUUUCUAAUAAUAAACCUUGUUCUACAUUCAGUUUAUAAACUUGACAAAGUAUGUUAGUGAUCUUGAUGUUUUUUGUUCUGCUUGAGCCUCUGAAAACAUCCCGUGUCUAAUUUGAUUUCAGUGUGUUUAUAUUCUGUAAAUGUACAUGGGUGACCUUUUACUACUGAACUUUGCAUAUUACAUGCAUCCAUUACUUCACAUUAUAGUUGCAUGAGCACUUAUUAAUAGGAUUGGCAACAGUGUUAUUAUAUAAGUUCUGGAUAGUGAAAACUCCCUUAUUGGCCACACUUCCAAGGAUGGCACCUGAAUCCAAAGAAUGGUAGGACUGCCCAAAUCAGAGAGCCCUGCACAUUGUUUCUGUCAGACUGGAGGCUGUCUCAAUGUGUGAUAAUAUAAACGAUAAGCAGUUUUGGUUUUUGGUGGCUUUUUUUUUUUUGGUUCUAUGAAAAGUCUGGUGAAAGGGUACUACGUCUUUCAAAAAACUCUUCUGAAAAUUAUUUUCAUCCAUCUGUCUAUCCAUUUAAAAAGUAUUGAAUUUUGUCCAGCUCUAGGCACUGUUGUAGAUACUAGAGAUCUAACAGUGGAAAAAAACAACAAAACAAAAAGCCCUGCUGAUAGAUCUUGUUAUUCUUCUAGUAGAGGGUGAUAAGUAAAAUACAUUAUGAGUUAGGUGAUCCACUCUAUGGAGAAAAAUUAAGCAGGGUAAGGGAAUAGAGAGUGGAAUAUGACUUAAAAUAGUGGUCAGUGUCUUCACUGAGAAGAUGACAUAUAAAAGGAUCUCAAAGAUGAUGAGGUAACAAAACAUAUAUCCAGGGGAAGACAAUUCUGGAUUGGUGAGAUUUAGCAGGUAUGAAAAUUCAUAAGAAGAUACCGUGAAUAAAUUUUAGGUCCUAUAAUAAUUUAUAGUUAGUAAGAAAUGAUGAACUUUUUUUAUUAGCUGUAAAAAUGAAAAUACAGUCUGAUUUUUAGGUAACUGAAUCCUGGGAAAGUCAAGAGCGCACCCGCUUUUUUCUUCCAGUAAAUGGCACCACCGUGUAUUUGAGUUUAUUCACUCUUCCUGCCCACUAACAUCAAUAGCCAGUCUAUAUCCAGUCUAGUAUAUUCUACCUUGUAUGUCAUUUCUUUUCCCUCCUCGUAAUUCCCAAUGACACUAGUUCAGUUUAGGUCUUGUCACUUUUCUCCUGGAUUAUUAUUAUAUCUUUUUUUUUUUUUUUUUUUGAGACAGAGUCUCGCUCUGUCGCCUGUGCUGGAGUGCAGUGGCGUGAUCUUGGCUCCCUGCAAUCUCCGCCUUCUGGGUUCAAGCGAUUCUCAUGUCUCAAUCCUGAGUAGCUGGGACUACAGGCAUGCACCACCACACCUAGCUAAUUUUUGUAUUUUUAGUAGAGACGGGGUUUCACUAUGUUGGCCAGGAUGGUCUUGAACUCCUGACCUCAAGUGAUCUGCCUGCCUCGGCCUCCCAAAGUGCUGGGAUUUCAGGCGUGAGCCACUGCACCCGGCCUAUUAUGUCUUCUUAAUGUCAGAUUCAUGUCUAAACCUCACUCACUUACCCCCUGCCAAGCCAAACAUGCUAUUGCUUUGCUAAACUUUUUUGCAGUUACCAUCAUCUUUUGUACGUUGUAUGAGGUAGAAAACCUUUAAUUCUUUGUUUCUUCCUCUGGAUUGUUUCUUCACUUUACAUAUUUGUUCAGUCAUCAAAUUUUACUGAUUGAUUAGAGUUUUCCAGUGCCUCUGGAAUUCAUUUAACUCUAUUUUACUCUCAUUGGUCUUUUUAGGGGCCCUCAUGUCCUCCUCCUUGUCUAUUAAAAAAGCUUAUUCACUAACUCAUUUCUCUUCCCCUAGUCUCUUUCACCUACAUAAUGAAGUUUAUCAUUUGCAUUGAUAACAAUUUUUUUUUUUUUCCAAAACGAAGUCCAAGCUCUCUGGCCUGGCAUUUAGAACCUACUUUCUCCAUAUCUUGAACACAUCGAACCCACAAUUCCUAUUUAAUGCCUCUAUUCCUUUGUUAUUUGCUCUAUUCAGUAUGACUCCCCUGCUAUCUUUUUUUAUGUAAGAAAUUUAUCUGAGUUGGUUUUCAAGCUCAGGUCAGACAUCUGUUGUACUCUAUAAACCUUCUGCCCUCAACUCUCCUAUAUCCGCCCCUGUACCCAAUAAAUAACUGAUCUGGCAUGUGCAUUCCCAUAGUAUGUUUUAAAAAUUUACACUACUAAUUCAUCAAUACCUUCUUACUUAAAAAAAAAUCCAACAAUGAGAGAUCUAUAAAGAUAAAAAGUAAAAAAAUGUGAACUUUGCUUUUUUAGAUUCUAAUCUCAUUUCACUCUCCAGUUGUCCUGUAUCUCUUGAGUAAAUAAAUACCUAGGAAUAGAAUUGCUGGGUCAUAUCACAUGUCUAGUAAUUUCAGAUUGGAUGUUAGAUACUGUAUUACAUUAUCCAUUGUCUGAUUUUUGUCCUUUUCCUUUAAAGAGUAUUGAAGGUUGUUUUGGGUGGCAGGUAAGCUGCUUGGAGAUCUUACUGAUCUUUUGAGGCUUUUUGUAUGUCUUUUAGGAUGGAUUUAACUGUUAAGCUAGCUUAGCCCUUCUGAAGUCCACUGAAUGUCCUAGGUCUUUAAGAAGGUCUCUCCAUUCUGGCUAGUCAGAACCGAAAUGUCUCCCAGUCCUAUAUGAACUGGGUAGCCAAAAACCCUAGUAGUCAUUCUUUGCCUGUAUUUGUGGAGUGUCACUAUGUAUUUGGAUAGUAUUCAGUAAGACUCGGGAAACCCCUGCAGGUUUCUAGAGCUUUUCUCUGUGUGGCUCCCACAUCACUGGUGCUCUGCUUCACAAAUAGCUGCUUCUGCUUCUCUGAACUUUAAUCUUUUUCUCCUCAACUUAACAAGGCUGCCAUACUAUGCUUGGUUUCUCUCACUCUACAUGAUGGACAAAACCUUAAGAGGUUAGAUGGUGACUUCUGCCAGAAAACCUGUUUGUUUUCCUUCCCUCAUGAUAUCAGUCCUGUGCUGCCUGCUGUCUCAUGUCUGAAUAUGGUUGGUUGAUCUAUUUUGUCCAGUUCUCUUGUUUCUGGGCACUAGUUUGGUACCAGGUACUCUAUUAGUAGAAUAAUAAAAUGACCAUCUGUGUGUCCAUCAGUCAGUUUGAACAAUUUUCAGUCUUUUUCCACUGGAGUAUAUUUAAGCACAUCCAAGAUAUCAUUAUUUCAUUUCAUCCAAAAAUACUUUUUAUUAUUGUAAGCAUUCCAGUAAACAAUGAUGAAUGCAAAUGAUGAAAUAUGAGGCCUGGAGUUUUAGGAAAAGAAAUCGUUCUGAGCCUUUCCAGAAUUAUGGUUGGAGAACUAAAGCCUCUUAGUCCCAGAAUUUACAUAGGACUGCCAGAACUUUCUAGAUCAAGCCUUGCACAUUUCAGAAUCAUCUCAAAUGGAUUCAUCCUCAUUUAUUGUAUGCCUGCUAUCUGUAAAACACUUGCUAUACACUGCUACUGAAGAUGCUAAUGAAUAAUUGUUUAAAGUUAAUGGCAAUAUAAAAUAACAGAUUGCCAGGUAAAUAUCUUGAAAAGUCAUAAUAGCAUUUCAGGGUAAAGUGAUUAGUUGUCAAGGGAAGUUUUGUAGAUAAGGAGACUUGAGUUCUAUACUUGGGAGAGAAGUCAGGACUUAGGUAAGUUAUGUUGCAAGGAAAAACACUAUAAUUAAUUGCAUUCUUGAAGUUUCUGUUCCCCCACACCCCAAAUCUAUUAGGUUAUUUGCCACAUUAUUCUUUUCUUUAGCUGGCACUUAAAGCAUUUGGUAUCUCCUGCACAGAAGAAUUUGCUCAAAGAAAUGGCUGUUGAAUUUGUGAAUCAGUUUUCUGUAUCACCUGAUCUAGCCCUCAAAGCAUACUUGACAUGCUUUAAAAGCAGUCUUCUUUUCUUUUAAGACUUCUGUGUAGUUUUUAUGCUACACUUGGUAUUGUGGUUUGAUUUUUGGUUUUUACCAAUUUGAUGAGAAAUUACUCCCCGCUCAGUGUCCUGGGAAGUUUGACUAGUGGUUGACCCAUCCCAUAGAAACAUUUUAUUUUUUUCAUGGCCCUUUAAGGGCCACUCAUUAACAUGAAUGCCUUAUCAUUCAUUGGAAUAGAAAACUGGGAGGCUUUACUUUUAGUUACAAAAGUUAAUGUAUGGAAAAUACAUUAAUAAAACCGGCUUAGCUUCAUUUUUCCUACUUUCUUGUGAUAUUUUUCUUAGACUUGCUAUUGAUACCUCAGAUAAAUAUCCAGCAGUUUAGAGAUGUGGAAAAAAAUAUGGCAGUUGGAAUCAGAGAGGCCCAGGUUCCAGUUCAGAUUCUGCUUUUUCCCAAGACUUUGGAAAAGCCAUUUUCUAAAGUUGCUUUCUGUGCUGUGUGUCUAUAAAAUGAGAAAAAUGAGUGAUUAGAUUCUUAAUAAGUUGCAACUGGUAUUGUUGUCUAGGUUGCCUUCUGAAUUAUGUAAAUAUAAUGUGCCUCCAUUGCAUAUUUAUGACAAUUUAUAAGUGUUUAAAAAAGAAGGGGAUUCUAGUUCAUUAACUGCGAGGUUUUAGAGUGAACUAGAAUUUGAAGAAUGACAAAACUUUAAGAGGUUGCCAAAAAAUACAGGUGUACUUGUUCAAAAGCAAGUCUCAGAUUGAGUCAUGUAUCAAAUGUAAGCAAUAACAGACUUGACUCCUCUGGGGAACUUAGGCAGAGUAUUCAUUUAUACAAUACUUGAAAAUUCCAAGUAUUAACAAAGAUAGCUUCUUUAAUAUAGCGAGAAACUCCUUACAUCAUAUCCUUGAAUAAUGUCAUAACAUCGAUGAGGGAAAAAAAUUGAUCCCUGGCCAGGGCCACUGUCAAUAUGGAAUUUUCAUAUUCUCCCUAUGUCUGUGUAGUACUGUAGUUUCCUCCCACAUCCCAAAGAUGUACGCUUUGGGUGAAUCAGCAUCUGCAUGGCCCCAGUCUGAGCGAGUGUGGGGUAUGUGUGUGAGUGCGCCCUCCAAUGGAAUGACAUCUGGUCCAAGGUGGGCUUCAGCUUUGGCCCCAAGCUGCUGGGAUGGGCCGUGGCCACCUGCAAUUCUGAACUGGAAUUAGUGGGUAAAUGUUUUUAUUCAUCUUUCUUAAAUGUAUGUAUAGCUUACAUUUAUUUCAAUGUCUUUUUUUUUUUUUCAAAAAACUGUUUGUAUAUUGCAUAUAUAACUAAAAUAUAAAAGCAACAUUUUAUAAAACUUUCUAGAGAGACAAAUUCCACACAAGUGGUAAGGGCAACCUAGUGUCUCUAGAUUUGUUCUGUUUCAUAAAUUGGAUUUUAACAAAUCCUAUGUAAAUCAAUUUUUGUAAAUAAAAUGUAAUUGUUGGAUUUUUCACAUGUUAGAUUUUUGCAAUAAUCUGAGAUUUACAACACUUUCUGAUGUAUGUUCACUCUGAUUCUGAAACUAAAUUAUAUUAUUGGAUUUCAUAUACAGUAUUAAAAUUAGUGGUGGUUUACCAAGAUUAAACUUUAAAGCAUAUCUGAAAGUUAUCUAUCUGUAAAUAAGACAAAUUGUCUACAGAAUUAGUUUUAUAUAGUCAGUGAUGUGUAAACCUCUUGGCUUUAAGAACCACAACAACUUUGAAUGCAUUAAGAAAACUGUCACACAAUUGAUCCGAAACUGCAUUAAGAAAAAAAUUCCUACUUUUUUUUUUUUUUUUCCUUUCACUGGUUUCUUGUCUCUCAGGGUCAUCGUUCCAUGGGCUGUCCCCACCCAACCCCACCAAGUUUCCUUCAUUGACAUUUCUGUUCUUUCCUUCACAAAUUCUGCCAUGGCUUGUAGGGAGAGCACCUGAUUAACCAAUACUGAGCUGGGAAUGACCGACACUUCUUAGCUAGUUCUAUAAAUUUUGUUAGUUUGUUUUUGUUAGCCCCAGUUAAUCUCAAAUAGAUAGAAAUUUAGAACAUUAUUGAGGGGAUUAUAAUGGGAUUAAUCCCUUUUGCCUAUCCCAUAAUGUAUUCAGCUGUUUCAUUUCUUUUUGUUCAUUUGUGAUUUUGUGUUUUCAAAGUAAAAAAUCUGAAUAUUUAUUUAGAGUUUACUUUGGAUUAAAAAUAUUCAAUUUAUUAGAGCUUCAAAAUAAUAACUGUAGCUCAAACUUUUAAGUUCCAUCUACAAAUCUUAAAAAUCUAUUCGUAAAUCUAGCAAAUUUCAACACUUUUAGAGGGGAAUCUUACAAAUUAAAUUCUCUUACGUAUAUUAAUGUAUAUUUAUAAAUAUGCCUUAUAAAUAUAUAAUAAAUUAUAUAUUUUGUUUCUUCUUAAAAUACUUGAAUUGUCUAACAAGCUUUGUACCAUUUCAUGAGCAGGUAUUUUUGCCAAAGCAUGAUAUAUGCAUUGUGUAAACACCUUCAUUCUGCACAAGUGCACACUAAAAACAAAGCUUGUGGGAAAAUCGUUGGAACAGAUCACUUAAAACUUCCUAUAACUUUGAACUAGAGGAGUCACAAAUAAUAAUCUUAAUAAAAGUUAGAAAAUAAUUAAAUUUUUUCUUUUCCAUGUAGUUUCACAAAGACAACUGCAAGUUAUAAAUAUUUUUUUUCAAAUAAGUAUAAUUUCCUACUGCUUCCCUACUCUUCACAUUCUUUUCCCCAGUUAGCUUACCUAGCUUUUAGUUCAGAUUCUUCUCAGAAUCGUAUGGUCAAAGUCUGGUGUUUAAUUUCCCUUCAUGUUUCUUCUCAAAAUUUAUCAAAACUAUCACUAUGACUUAAGUUGGCUGGGUUCUAUUUCAUUAGUGCAAGUAAACAAUAACUUGUUAUCACCCAUUUGUGGUAAAACUGUGGUAUAGCUGGCUCUUCUGUUUGAGACCUAUAGAAAAGCUCUGAAUGUUUUUUUUCUUUCAUGAGUGGAUGUGUACAUAGCACUCCUGAUGGAGAUAUUUAUCUUUUUUAUGGGCAUCUAUAUUGAAUCCUUUGGAGUAUAUCGAUUUAAAUGCAAAGUGUAGCUUAGAAAUAAAUGUUUGGGCUGGGUGAGGUGGCUCACGCCUGCAAUCUCAGCACUUUGGGAGGCCCAAGGCGGGUGGAUCACUUGAGGUCGGGAGUUCAAGACCAGCCUGACCAACAUAGCAGAACCCCCGUCUCUACUAACAAUACAAAAAUUAGCUGGUGUGGUAAUCCCGGCUACUCAGGAGGCUGAAGCAAAUUGCUUGAACUGGGAGGUGGACAUUGCAGUUUGCCGAGAUUGCACCACUGCACUCCAGCCUGGGUGACAGAGCAAGACUCCAUUUAAAAAAAAAAAAAAAGAAAAGUUCAGUUACAUUUUCUCUUGAAAAUUCAGGUUUUUGUUUUCUAUCCAUCUUCCUUACCUUGUAUAGUUUAACUUAACUUUUGCUCUGUAUAAUUCGUACUAUAACAUUAGUAUGAAUAUGGUAGGUAGUGCAUGUCAAAUCUAUUAUCUGUUCUUCCAAACAAUUUUGCUUUUAGUGAGAAAACCAUCAUAAUUAAAAUAUUGAAGCUGGUUAGUUUCUCAAGCACAUGACUGGGAUCAAAAGCAAAGGAGUAACUGUUAACAUUUAAUACACUCAAAAUGUCAAAAAACAUACGUGCAUACAUCCCACUUAUGCAGGGAUCCACGUAUUAAACAUCAUCAAUUGCCUGGAAUAGCUAAGACUCAGGAAAUAAGGCCUCCAAGGGGACACUCAUCUUUACUCAUUUAAGACAUUUGUUGGUUUUGGGCUAUAUACAAGGCAAUGGUGUGAAUUAGAGUUGAUUUUUUCCCAGUCUGAAGCUCAUAGUUUAUUAAGGGGACAAAAGCUAAAUUCAGAUAAUAUCAAAUAUACUGUAAAAGUGAUGUGUACUCUAAAGGAGCUACAGAUAAAUAGCUUUGGGAGGCAGUUUAGAAAGGGAAUAUACUUUCAGUGUAUUAUUGAGGAAUUCUUUGUAAAGAGAGUAGCAUCUGAGCUGAGUCAUGAGGUAUAUUAGUCUAUUCUCACACUGCCAUAAAUAAACACCUAAGACUGGGUAAUUUAUAAAGAAAAGAGGUUUAAUUGGUUCACAGUUCCGCAGGCUAUACAGGAAGAAUGGCUGGGGAGGCCUCAGGAAACUUACAGUCAUGACAGAAGGAGAAGGGGAAGCAGGCACCUCUUACACGGCCAGAGCAGGAAGCCGGGGAGAGGUGCUACACACUUACACACUUUUUUUUUGUUUUGUUUUGUUUUUGUUUUUGUUUUUGUUUUUGUUUGUUUGUUUGUUUGAGACAGAGUCUCACUCUGUUGCCAGGCUGGAGUGCAGUGGCACCAUCUCGGCUCACUGCAACCUCCGCCUCCCGGGUUGAAGCAAUUCUCCUGCUUCAGCCUCCUGAGUAGCUGGGACUACAGGCACACGCCGCCAUGCCCGGCUAAUUUUUUUUGUGUGUGUAUUUUAGUGGAGACAGGCUUUCACCCUGUUGCCCAGGCUGGUCUCGAACUCCUGAGCUCAGGCAUUCUGCCCGACUUGGCCUCCCAAAGUGCUAGGAUUACAGGCGUGAGCCACUGCAUGCAACUGAGCUACACACUUUUAAACAACCAGAUCUCACGAUAACUUACUAUCACAAGAACAGCACCAAAGGGGAAAUUGCCCUCAUGAUCCAGUCACCUCCCACCAGGCCCCACCUCCAACGUUGGGGAUUACAAUUUGACAUAAGAUUUGUGUAGGGACAGAGACCCAAACCAUGUAAUUCCACCCUUGUCCCCUGCCAAAUCUCAUGUCUUUCUCACAUUUAAAAUACAAUCAUGCCUUCACAAGAGUCCCCCAAAGUCUGAACCCAUUCCAGCAUUAACUCAAAAGUCCGAAGUCUCAUCUGAGACAAAACUAGUCUCUUCUGCCUAUGAGCCUGUAAAAUCAAAAACAAGUUAAUAACUUCCAAGAUACAAUGGGAAUACAGACAUUGGUUAAUACUCCCGUUCCGAAAGGGAAGAAUCAGCCAAAAGAAAGGGACUAUAAGCCCCGUGCAGAUCUGAAACACAGUAGGGCAGUCAUUAAUUCUUAAAGCUCCAAAAUAACCUCCUUUGACUCCAUGUCUCACAUAGCAUUAAGUACAUUUACAGUGUUUUGUACAACUAUCACAAUUACCUAGUUCCAGAACUUUUACAUCACUCCAGGCAGAAACCAUGGAUUCAUUAAGCAGUCAUUCCCUGUUCUCUUCUGCUCUCAGCCCCUAGAACCAUACAUUUGUUUCUUGUCUGUGUCUCUCUGGAUUUGCCUAUUCUGGAUACACUAUAUAAAUAUAAUACAGCAUGUACCUUUUGUGUCUUAUUUAAUUGCUGGAUACUUUGUAUAAAUGGAAUCACACACUAUGUACCUUUUGUGUCUUCUUAAUGUAAUGUUUUCAAGGUUAAUUCGUGUUUUAGCAUGUAUCAGUACUUCGUUUCUUUUAUGGCUGAAUAAUAUUUUGUUAUAUGGAUUUACCACAGGGUGUUUAUCCAUGAAUCAGGUGAUGGCCAUUGAGGUUGUUUUCACUUUUUGGCUAUUGGAACAGUCCUGCUAUGACUAGGAGUGUUCAUAGCAGUUGUUCAUGUACAAUUUGUAUUUGAACACCUGUUUUCAAUUAUUUUUGGGUAUAUACCUGGAAGUAGAAUUGCUAGGUUACAUGGUAAUUCUAUGUUUAACUUUUUGAGAAACUGCCAGACUGUUUUCCCACAAGCCAUAUGUGAAGGUUCUGGUUUCUCCAUAUCCUCAUCAACAUUUGUUAUUUUCUGGGUUUUUUUUUUUAUUAUAUUAGGGUCAUCCCAAUGAAUGUGAAAUAGUAUCUCAUUAUGGUUUUGAUGUGUAUUUCCCUAAUGAUUAAUGACAUUGAACAUACUUUCAUUUGCUCUUUGGCCAUUUGUGUAUCUUCUCUAGAUAAAUAUCUAUUCAAGUCUUCUUCCCACUGUCUUUUUUUUUUUUAUUUUUUUAAAGAAAGCUUCUUGCUCUGUCUUCCAGGCAGUGUCACAAUCAUAGCUCACUGCAUCCUUGAUUUCUUGGGCUCAAGCAAUCCUCUCACCUCAGUCACCAGAGUAGCUGGGACUACAGGCAUGCACCACCACACCUGGCUAAUUUUUUGAUUUUUUUGUGAAGUUGGGAUCUCACUACAUUGUUCAAGCUAGUCUCAAACUCCUGGGCUCAAGCAAUCCUCCUGUCUUGGCCCCCCAAAGUGCUGGAAUUACAAGCAUGAGCCACCAUGCCCUGCCUCUCCCUUCUUUUUAAUUGGUUUGUUUAUCUUUGAGUUAUAAGAAUUAUUUAUAUAUUCUGGAUACUACAUCCUUUUAAGAUACAUGAUUUUCAUAUUUUUUUUCUCAUUGUCUGGGCUUUUCACUUUCUUGGUAGUGUAUUUUGCACAAAAAAGUUUAAUUUUGAUGAAGUCCAAUUUAUAUAUAUAUUUUGUUCCUUACAGUUUUUUUAUAUCUAGAAAACAAUUGCCAAAUGCAAGGCCAUGACAAUUUACGCCUAUAUUUUCUUCUAUUUUUUUAAGAAUAGUUUUAGCUCUUAUAUUUAGAGUUUUUAUUCAUUUUGAAUUAUUUUUUACUUAUGAUGUGAGAUAAGGAUCCAACUUAAUUCUUUCGUAAAUGGUUAUUCAGUUGUCUUAGUACAGAGAAUGUUGUUUCCCCUGUUGAGUGCACUUGGCACCUUUGCCAAUAAUCAAUUGACCAUAGGUAUACAGGUUUAUUAUUAGGCUCUUAAUUCCAUUCCAUUGAUCUGUAUGUCUGCCCUUGUAUCAUUACCACACUGUGUUGGUUACUGUAGCUUUGCAGUAGGUUUUGUGAUCAGGAAAUGUGAAUUCUCCAACUUUGUUCUUCUUUUCAAGAUUAUUUUGGCUCUUCGGGGUUCCUUGCCUUUCUGUAUGAAUUUUAGGAUCAGCUUUCCCAUUUCUGUUUUUUUUUUUUUUUUUUUUAAAAGAACAUUGGGAUUUUGGUAGAAAUUGCAUUUAAUCUAUAGCUGUUUGGGAAGUAUUAUCGUAACAAUAUUAAAUAUUCCAUUCAUGAACAUAAUAUACCUUUCCAAUUUCUUAGUUCUCCCUUAAUUUAUUUACGCAUACAACUCUUACUCAUCCUUGGGUCAGUUUAUUCCCAAGUAUUUUAUUCCUUUUUGAUGCUAUUGUAAAUGGAGUUGUUUUCUGAAAUUUUUAUUGCUAGCGUAGAGAAAUAUAUACGAUUUCUGUGUUGAUCAUGUACUACAGCUUUGAUGAAUUUAUUAGCUCUAAUAACUCUUCUGUGGAUUCUUUAGAAUUUUCUAUAUAUACUAUACUAUUAUGACAUCUUUGAAUAAAGAGAGUCCCAUUUUUUCCGUUUCUGUUGGAUGACUUUUCUUUUUCUUACUUGAUUGCUGUCUAGAAUGUCCAGUAUUAUGCUGAACGGAAGUAGUGAGAGCAGCAUUCUUGUCUCAUGCAUGAUCGUAGCGGGAAAACUUUCAGUCAGUAAACAGUCAUUUACUGUUGAGUAAGAUGUUAGCUGUGCGCUUUAUCAUAUAUGUCCUUUAUCAUUUUGAAGAAGUUCCCUUCCUUUCCUCAUUUGUUGAGUGUUUUUAUCUUAAAAGAUUAUUACUAUUUUUUCAGAUGCUUUUUCUGCAUGAAUUGAAAUCAUUCUGGGAUUUUUCCCCUUCAUUCUAUUAAUAUGAUUACAUUGUAUUACAUUGAUUUUCAUGUGUUGAACCACCAUUGUAUUCUUAGGCUAAAGCCCACUUGGUAGUGGUGGAUAAUCCUUUUAAUAUGCUACUGGAUCCAGUUUGCUAAUAUUUUGUUCAGGAUUUUUUUUACAUCUAUAUUCAUAAGGUAUAUUGAGCCAUGGUUUCCUUUUCUUGCAGUGUCUUUGUCUGACUUUGGUAUCAGGGUAAUUCUGGCCUCAUAGAAUGAAUUAGAAGUCCGGGGAUGGUGGCUUAACGCCUGUAAUCCCAGCAUUUUGGGAGGCCAAGGUGGGCAGAUCACGAGGUCAGGAGAUCUAGACCAUCCUGACCAACAUGGUGAAACUGCAUCUAAAAUAAAAAAAUUAGCUGGGCAUGGUGGCACAUGCCUGUAAUCCCAGGUACUCGGGAGGCUAAGGCAGGAGAAUUGCUUGAACCAGGGAGUCGGAGGUUGCGGUGAGCUGAGAUCGCACCACUGCACUCCAGCCUAGCGACAGAGCAAGACUCUGUCUCAAAAAAAAGGAAUGAAUUAGAAAGUGUUCCCUCCUCUUACCUAUUUUUUUUUAAUAACAUCUUGAGAAGGAUGAAUGUUCAUUCUUAUUUAAAUAUUGUAUAGGUCACUAAUUAAGCCAUCUUGUUUUGGGUUCUUCUUUAUUGGGAGGUUUUUUGAUUAGUGACUCAAUUUCAUUACUUAUUAUAGGUCUAUUCAUAUGUUUUAUUUCCUCGAGUCAGUUGGGAAAUUUGUGUGUUUCUAGGAAUUUGUCCAUUUAACAUAGGUUAUCUAACUUGUUAGCAUUCAGUUGUUUACAAUAUUCUCUUAUAACCCAUACUAUUUUUUUGUAUGAUCAGUAAUAAUAUUCCCACUUUCAUUUCAGACUUAUAAAGUCUUCUUUUUCCUUAGGUUUUUCAAUUGUAUUGAUGUUUUCAAACAACCAACUUGCUUUAAUUGAUUUUUCUCUGUUUUUCUAUUCUCGAUUUCAUGUAUAGCCACUCUAAUUUUUAUCACAUCCAUCCUUCUGCCAGCUCUUUUACUAGUUCCAUAAGGUAUAAAGUUAGGUUACUGAUUUGAAAUCUUUUUCUUAAUAUAGGCAUUUUACCUAUAAAUUUCUCUCUGAGGACUUCAUUCACUGUAUCCCAUAACGUUGCAUGUUUGUUUUCAUUAGUUUCAGAGCAUUUCCUGAUUUCCCUUUUGGUUCUUCUUUGAGUCAUUGAUUGUUUUACAGUGUAUUUUGAAUUUCCACAUAUUUGAAUUUUCUAGUUUUUCUUUUACUGAUUUUUAGUUAUAUUCCAUUUGGUUAGAGAAGAUACUUUAUGUGCUUUCAGUCUUUUAAAAUUUAUUAAGACUUUUUUGUGGUUUAAUAUCCAUUCUGUCUUGGAGAAUGUUCCAUGUGCAUUUGAGAAUAAUAUGUAUUCUGCUGUUGGGUGGCAUAUUCAGUAUGUGUCUUAGGUCUAAGUGGUUUAUAUAGUGUUAUUUAACUUCUCUAUUUCCUUAUUUUCUGUCCAGUUCUAUCCAUUAUUGAAAGUGGGGUAUUGAAGUCUCCAACAUUAUUACACAUCUAUUUUUCCCUUCAGUUUUGUGUUCUUUCUUCAUAUAUUAAUAUUUUGUGGCUCUGAUGCUAUAUUUGAAUCUCUUUAUAGGUGUGGUAUCUUCUUGCUAGAUUGACUGUUUGAUCAUUAUAAAAAUCCUUCUUUGUCUCUUGUGAUAGUUCCUAAAGUCUUUUGUUUUUUUGUUUGUUUGUUUGUUUGUUUCUGAUUUUACCACAGCCACCCUACUAUUUGCAUGGAAUAUAUUUUUCCUUCCUUCCACCUUCAACUUGUUUCCUUGGAUCUAAAGUAAUUUUCUUGUAGACAGCUUAUAAAUGGACUCAUUUGGUUUAUUCGAAUCCAUUCUGAUAAUGCUUGCCUUUUAAUGAAUGCAUUUAAUCCAUUUACAUUAAAGUACUUACUGAUAAAGAAGGAUUUCUGCCAUUUUGCUAUUUGUUUUCUAUUAUGUCUGUAUCUUUUUUGUCCUGGGUUCCUCCACUGCUGCCUUUUUGUUGUUGUUGUUGUUGUUUUUAUUGUUGUUGUUGGUUUGAUUUUUUUGCAUUGUACCAUUUCAACUCCUUUCUCAUUUCCUUUUUUGUACAUGUUUUAGUUAUUAAUGGUUACCUUGGGGAUUAAAUUAACAUCUUGCAUGUACAACAGCCUAGUUUGAAGUAAUACCAACUUAGCUUCAAUAAUAUCUCAAAACUAUGUUCCCGUACAUCUCCCUCUCUCCCUUUUUAUGUUGUUGUUAUGACAAAUUACAUCUUUAUACAUUGUGUAACUGUUAACAUAGAUAUAUAAUUACUGUUUUAUGCACUUGUCUUUUGAGUCAUAUAGGGAAAAAAAGGCAGAUUUCUGAACCAAAAAUACUGCUGGCUUUUAUAUUUACCUAUGUAAUUACUUUUAUCAGUGUUCUUUAUUUUCUUACAUGGGUUUGAGUUAUUGCCUCUUGUUUUUUCAGGCUGAAGAACUUCCUUUAGCAUUUCUGGUAGUUCAGGUCUACUUGUGACAAAUUCCCUCAACUUUUUGUUUAUCUGGAAAUUCAUUAAUUUCUUUUUUGUUUUUGAAGGAUAAUUUUUCUAGAUAUUUCAGCACUUGAAAUAUGUCAUCCCACUGUUCUCUGGCCUCCAUGGUUUCCUAUGAAAAGUUGGCUGUCAGUCUUACUUGGGAUCUCUUGUAUGUGAGGAGUCACAUACAUCUCUUGCUGCUUUCAAGAUUCUCUUCGUUUUUUUGACAGUUUGAACAUGAUGUGUCUCUGUGUGCAUCUUUUAAAAUUUAUCCUACUUGGAGUUUCUUGGAAGAAAGACUCUUGGCUUUCUCAGAUUUGGAAAGUUUGUAACCAUGAUUUCUUCAUAUAUUCUCUUUUCUCUCUCCUUGCCUUUGGACUUCCAUCAUACAGACAGGCGUUGGUAUUUAUGAUGUUGUUCCCAUAAGUCUUUAAACUGGGUCUAUUUUUUUUUCAUUCUUUUUUCCUAUUUCUUGGAUUCCAUAGUUAAUGAAAUCACUCAUGUCGAAUAGUCACAAACUGUUAAUUUGUUGAGUUUUACAGGACAAAAAUCUAACAAUUGUUAGUUACUUGAUUUUGUACACUAUAUUAGUCAGCAUAGCUUAAAUCAUCACAGUAGAGGAUUAAAAACAAAACAUGUACCAAGUGUUGGCUCUUAAAUCUUCUGUUCAGAAAUGACACAAAUCACUUCCCCUCAUAUUUUAUAGGCCAAAGUAAAUCAUGUGGCCACACCUAAUUUUAAGAAGGCAGGAAACUGCAGUUCUGCCGUCUGUCCAGAUACGAAAAACAUUAACAUUUACAGUGUGUGUUCCCUUCCCUACUCCAUCCCCAAUCCAUUCCUUAGCAUUCAUUCCAUUAUUUCUACGUGCAGACAGAGGUUACUGUGUUAGUCUCUUUAACUCUAAUUUUCAGUUGCUUAGAGCCUUAAAUAUUAGAGUUUGAUUAUCAGCUCCCUUACUUUCUUAGCUUUGUGAUCAAGAGCAAAGUUCUCAAUAUUUGUACGUUUCAGUUUUCUCUCUGAAAAAGUGGAGAUAAUUCCUGUCUCAAAAGAUUACAAAUGAUUGGUUGAGAGGAUGUGUAUAGAACGUUUUGUACACUGUUUCAUACAUAGUAAAUGCUCUAUUCCUAUUCUCCUGGCAUUCAGUGCUUUCAUAAUCUGGCUUCAACUUAUUCUUCUAGCCUCAUCUUCUGUGACUCUCUUCCAGUCAUCUGAUGCUGUACCUUAUCAAAUUAUAGUUGAAUUCUAAGUAAUAAUAUUUUUUAUGAGAAAGUCAGAAUUUUUUUGUUACUGUAAUUUUUUAAAGUUUGCUCUAUUUUAGUAUGUUUGGAAGACAGGAUGGAAACUUUCCUGCGAGAUGUAUCUCUAAUUUUAUAAUGGAAGUCAUGAAGAAAUUAGAAUUUACUUAAAUUUGCUUUAAAGUUCUUGUAAUACUUUAGUUGUAAUAAAUGAGAAUAUUCAUAUAAAGAAAAACACGGUUUCCAGUUUUAAGAUAGGUAAUGUGGUUUCAAUUCUUUCUCUUGAUAAUCACCAACAGAAAAAAAGCUGAAAUAAAAUUCCCAUCUUUAAUUUAAACUAGAGGUAUCUCCAACCCUUGAGCUAAAAAUCCAAAGAGAAAGAUAAAUAACUAAGGAAGAGCAUCAAACUUGAGCGCUUAAGAACCUACAGGAUACUGAUAAAAAGCACCUUGUUUUACCUGCAAACUCAGAAAGGCUUAGAGCUUAGAAGGACUGGUACUACAGAAUAUAGGAGUGAGGCAGGGGCCAUCAACAUAGAGAUUGCUUGAAAACACUGAAUAAGGAUUCCUAUGUUCCCACCUCACAGGAAAUAUACUGUCUGGUUUAACAAUAUGUAUUAUAUUUAACAGAAGAGUGAGAUGCUAAAGUUGUCAUAGUGCCUCUUUACCCUGCUUGGCUCCAGACUUCUGUCUUUCACGCUUUGAUAUCCCAGGCAGGUUUGAGGGAUCCUUCCUGGAGAAAUGGAACCACUGAAGAAAAACUGCUCAACAGAGGAAGUCCACAAAUGAAGGGGACACCCCAUUUUAAGGAAGAACAGUGUGCUCCAGCAUUAAAUUUGGAGAUGAGGAAAAUACUGGAUUUACAAGCACCCAUCAUGAGUUUGCAGUCUGUGUUGGAAGAUCUCCUGGUUGCUACUUCUGAUGGACUUCUUCAUCUUAUUCACUGGGAAGGAAUGACAAAUGGAAGGAAAGCCAUUAAUCUUUGCACAGUACCCUUUUCAGUAGACCUGCAGUCAUCUAGAGUAGGUUCAUUCCUGGGCUUCACAGACGUACACAUCAGAGACAUGGAAUACUGUGCCACACUUGAUGGGUUUGCUGUUGUAUUUAAUGAUGGUAAAGUUGGAUUUAUUACACCAGUGUCAAGUAGAUUUACUGCAGAGCAGCUUCAUGGAGUUUGGCCACAAGAUGUUGUUGACGGAACGUGUGUAGCAGUAAAUAACAAGUAUCGACUAAUGGCAUUUGGCUGUGUGAGUGGUUCUGUGCAGGUCUAUACAAUAGAUAACAGCACUGGAGCCAUGCUGCUAUCUCAUAAAUUAGAGCUAACAGCAAAACAGUAUCCUGACAUUUGGAAUAAAACAGGAGCUGUUAAAUUGAUGAGAUGGUCUCCUGACAAUAGUGUUGUAAUAGUGACCUGGGAAUACGGAGGCCUUUCUUUAUGGAGUGUUUUUGGAGCACAGCUGAUUUGUACACUUGGAGGAGAUUUUGCUUAUAGGUCUGAUGGCACCAAAAAAGAUCCCCUUAAGAUCAACUCUAUGAGCUGGGGUGCAGAAGGCUAUCACCUAUGGGUAAUCAGCGGAUUUGGUUCUCAAAACACUGAAAUUGAGUCUGACCUCAGGAGUGUAGUUAAACAGCCCAGCAUCCUGUUAUUUCAGUUUAUUAAGAGUGUACUCACUGUAAACCCUUGUAUGAGUAACCAAGAGCAGGUGUUGCUUCAGGGUGAGGAUCGCUUGUACUUGAACUGUGGAGAGGCUUCACAAACCCAGAAUCCCAGGAGUUCUUCAACACACUCUGAGCAUAAGCCCAGUCGAGAAAAGAGCCCAUUUGCAGAUGGAGGUUUAGAGUCUCAGGGAUUAAGCACUUUACUUGGACAUCGGCAUUGGCAUGUUGUACAGAUUUCCAGCACCUAUCUAGAGAGCAAUUGGCCUAUACGGUUUUCAGCUAUUGAUAAGCUUGGACAGAAUAUUGCUGUGGUUGGCAAGUUUGGUUUUGCACAUUACUCUUUACUCACCAAAAAAUGGAAACUUUUUGGAAACAUUACCCAGGAGCAAAAUAUGAUCGUGACAGGUGGCUUAGCCUGGUGGAAUGAUUUUAUGGUCCUUGCGUGUUAUAACAUAAAUGACCGUCAAGAAGAGCUUAGAGUAUACUUGCGAACAUCAAAUCUGGACAAUGCCUUUGCUCAUGUCACCAAAGCACAAGCAGAAACAUUACUGCUUAGUGUCUUCCAGGACAUGGUAAUAGUAUUUAGAGCAGACUGUUCAAUAUGCCUUUACAGUAUUGAAAGAAAAUCUGAUGGUCCAAAUACUACUGCUGGUAUUCAAGUUCUUCAGGAGGUUUCCAUGUCACGCUACAUUCCUCACCCUUUCCUGGUGGUAUCUGUCACUCUGACAUCAGUGAGUACAGAGAAUGGAAUCACCUUGAAAAUGCCACAGCAGGCUCGUGGUGCAGAGAGCAUUAUGUUAAACCUGGCAGGACAGCUCAUCAUGAUGCAGAGGGACAGGUCAGGCCCACAGAUCCGGGAGAAGGACAGUAACCCUAAUAACCAAAGGAAACUUCUGCCAUUCUGUCCUCCUGUUGUACUAGCCCAGUCUGUUGAAAAUGUCUGGACAACGUGUCGAGCAAAUAAACAGAAACGUCACCUUCUGGAGGCCCUCUGGCUGAGCUGUGGUGGUGCAGGGAUGAAAGUUUGGCUCCCUCUCUUCCCUAGGGAUCACCGCAAGCCCCAUUCCUUCUUGUCCCAGCGGAUCAUGCUGCCUUUCCACAUCAACAUUUACCCGCUAGCUGUUCUGUUUGAAGAUGCUUUAGUCCUUGGUGCUGUCAAUGACACUUUGCUCUAUGAUUCUUUAUAUACUCGGAACAAUGCUAGAGAACAGCUGGAGGUGCUCUUCCCUUUCUGUGUUGUGGAGAGAACCUCUCAGAUCUACCUCCACCACAUUCUACGUCAACUUCUGGUCAGAAACCUUGGGGAGCAAGCCUUGCUCUUGGCCCAGUCCUGUGCCACAUUACCUUACUUCCCUCAUGUGCUGGAGCUCAUGCUCCAUGAAGUACUGGAAGAAGAAGCUACCUCACGGGAGCCCAUUCCCGACCCUCUGCUUCCCACUGUGGCAAAAUUUAUCACUGAGUUCCCCCUCUUCCUGCAGACAGUUGUCCAUUGUGCCAGGAAGACCGAAUAUGCCCUGUGGAAUUACCUUUUUGCAGCUGUUGGAAACCCUAAGGACUUGUUUGAGGAGUGUUUGAUGGCUCAGGAUUUGGACACAGCUGCCUCUUACCUUAUUAUCUUACAGAAUAUGGAAGUCCCUGCAGUAAGUAGGCAACAUGCUACCCUUCUAUUCAACACAGCACUAGAACAAGGCAAGUGGGACCUUUGUCGACACAUGAUUCGAUUUCUUAAAGCCAUUGGCUCUGGAGAAUCUGAGACACCUCCAUCCACACCCACAGCUCAGGAACCCAGUUCAAGUGGUGGAUUUGAGUUCUUCAGGAAUCGAAGCAUCAGUUUAUCCCAGUCAGCUGAAAAUGUUCCUGCCAGUAAAUUCAGUUUACAGAAAACACUAAGUAUGCCAUCUGGUCCCUCUGGAAAAAGAUGGAGCAAAGACAGUGACUGUGCUGAGAACAUGUAUAUUGACAUGAUGCUCUGGAGACAUGCUCGGCGCCUCUUAGAAGAUGUGAGGUUAAAGGACCUUGGCUGCUUUGCAGCCCAGCUGGGCUUUGAACUAAUUAGUUGGCUAUGCAAGGAACGUACCCGAGCCGCCCGGGUAGACAACUUUGUAAUAGCCCUGAAGAGACUCCACAAAGAUUUCCUGUGGCCACUUCCAAUCAUCCCAGCCUCUUCUAUCAGUUCUCCUUUCAAAAAUGGAAAAUACCGAACUGUGGGAGAGCAGCUGUUAAAGUCUCAAUCAGCUGACCCAUUUUUGAACCUUGAGAUGGAUGCUGGCAUCUCCAACAUCCAGCGAAGUCAGAGCUGGCUCAGCAACAUUGGCCCCACCCAUCAUGAGAUAGACACAGCUUCAUCCCAUGGACCACAAAUGCAAGAUGCCUUCUUGUCACCUUUAUCUAAUAAAGGUGAUGAAUGCAGUAUUGGUUCAGCCACAGACUUGACUGAAAGUAGCUCCAUGGUGGAUGGCGACUGGACAAUGGUGGAUGAAAAUUUCUCUACACUCAGUUUAACUCAGUCAGAGCUGGAGCACAUUUCCAUGGAGUUGGCCAGUAAAGGGCCUCAUAAAUCCCAGGUCCAGCUUCGGUAUUUGCUACACAUUUUCAUGGAGGCAGGGUGCCUAGACUGGUGCAUCGUUAUAGGCCUGAUUCUUAGAGAAUCCUCAAUAAUCAAUCAGAUUUUGGUUAUUACACAGUCUUCAGAGGUAGAUGGAGAGAUGUUACAGAACAUAAAGACAGGGCUCCAUGCAGUGGACCGAUGGGCCUCUACAGACUGUCCUGGAUAUAAGCCAUUUUUAAACAUCAUUAAGCCACAACUGCAGAAGCUCAGUGAGAUAACAGAAGAGCAGGUCCAGCCAGAUGCCUUCCAACCAAUAACUAUGGGUAAGACUCCAGAACAGACUAGCCCCCGGGCAGAGGAGAGCAGGGGCUCCUCCAGCCAUGGAAGCAUCCCCCAGGGUGAAGUUGGAAGCAGCAAUAUGGUCAGCCGGAAAGAGGAGGACACAGCCCAAGCAGAGGAGGAAGAACCUUUUCAGGAUGGGACUUACGACUGUUCUGUGUCCUAACAGUGAGGUUCCAUCACAAAGGGGCAGUAUUAAUUAGCAGCAGCGUGCAGCUCAGUACGUUGUAACAUAGUUGGAUGAUUUAACAGGAGAACUCAGUUCAGAGACUCUUCGGUAAGUAUUAGUAGAUUUUAACUAAUUCUUUCUUGUCUAAGAAAUCUUUUUGACUCCAUAAAAAUGUGAUAUAAAGCAUCUUUCAUAAAAAAAUUUUAAGCUGCAGUGAAAAGUAAAUAUUGUACAGAUGUACAUGAGAAUAUUUUGGUUUUACUCAAAGGUUGGUAGCUCUUAAACCACAGGAAUUGUUUUGCCCCAGGUGAGCUUACUUUUUCACUACUUACAUCUUCUCACAUUUCCCGGUUCUGCAUUAUGUCCAGAUUGCUUUUUAAAAAAUAAAUGCUAAGGUGCUUGCUAUAGUCUGUCAGGUACUUGAGCUACCUGUUUGCUCCCUUGGAUACAGCUGGACUCUUUAAUCAGUCCUCCUGAAUAGAUUGCUACCCUGGGGCACAAUAUGUGCCAGUGUGAUGGAAACAUUCUCCUUGGCUUUACUAGCCAGUCAAAUCCCAGUCCAGAAUUGAUGGAAGCUAUUUACCUGUGAGUUAAUGUGCUUGUUUUAGCAAGCUUGAUUCCCAUUAGACCAAUGUGGGCAGAGGUCUGAGGGGGUUCUUCUCAAUUUUGCUGUUAGAUACCACUAAACUAUUUUGUAUUAAAGAACAGUAUCUUUUUGUGAAUACUCUUGUGUAAAUAUAUUCAAAGGCACUGUUCAUAUUUUAGGGCUUGUAUUAUAAUUUGCAAGGUUUUAAUGCUGGAUUCUGCAUGUCUACACAUACAAAGACAGGGCUUGCUCCUCUGCAAAACUGAGGAAGACAGGUUUAUUGGCUUGGUCAUGAAGUAACAGAAAUGGUCACACUGAUCAUGAAAUGCAGCAAGUUUUGUGCAAAUUAACAUAGUCUCUUAUUUAUUGCUUUUGUAAAUUGAAUAAAGAUGGACUUCUAUGUAAAUAGACUGCUGAAUCCUGUAUUACCACGGCUACUAAAAAUUAGUGUGUAAAGAAUGCAUUCUUCAUUGUAAACUUAAAGUAUUUUAUGUACUUCUAGAAAUGACUUAAAUUUGUUUUCAUACAUUAUGAAAACAACUGCAUACUCCUUAAUUGCUUUAAACACCCAUCCACUGUAUGUAAUUCUAAUUACCUUAUAACAGUAUUAAGACAGCUUGUUUGUACUGUGCAAUUUGAACAAGGAAUGCAAUGUUAUUUUUUACAAAAAACAAACUUGUUUAUUUUUAUAAUAACGAUGUAUUUGAUGUGGACCAAAUUCGUACCACUAUCUAAAAUAGCCUCUUUUCUCAUAGUGCAGUUGUAGUUUAGAAACAAAACUUGGUCCUCUCUCCUUGCUUUUUAAAGUAAAUGGCUAGAUUUAGUUGUCUUAGCCAGGUUUCCUUUGAAGAGAAACUCAAAACCAUUUUGAAACUGCUUAGUUCAGAAUACAUCGAAGUAUUUAAAAUUACUGAGUUGGGUAAUUUACUAUCAUUUACUUUUUACAUUACAAGUGCAAUAAUAUUUCACAAAAUGAAACUCCCGAAUGGGUGGAGUAUGUGAUUAUUGGUACCUGGUCCUUCUGGUGCUAUUUUUAUUUAAGUCUUUGUUUCAAACCACCUUUCCCUGAAUCUUAAAGAUAAUGUUUUGCAUGUGAGUACAUGCAGCCCAGCAAGAAACUAAACUGAACUCUCUUCUCCUAUCCUAGUCCAUUAAGGAGAAGAACCAGCAUUGCUUUUGUGUUUGGUGUGAAUAUUCAGUCAAUAAAAAUGAUUUACCAUUAUAAAGAGCUGUGAUCUUUUCAAGUAUCUGAAAUAAAACACUGUGCUGCUGAGUUCAUCUCAAACAUUCUUGAAAGCAGGGCACCAGUAUAAGUUAACUGUAUUCCUGUGGGUUAGGCCGUGAAUGAAUCAUUUCUUUUAUACAAUAUUCUUUUACAACUAAUAGAGAUAGGAGGCCCCCAGGCAAGAAGUUUGGCAGGUUUACAGAAAAUUUGGUAAUUUAUUUGUUAUAUACCUUAAUUUUUAAAAACCCAUUUUUAUUGUGGUGUUUGGUUCACAUAUCAACUGUUUAAGCCAUAAUUUUAGCCAAUGAAUUUAAAUAUUCAGUAUAACUAUUUGAGGUUUACUAGAUGCAUUUAUUAAUAAAUUAUUUGCUGAAACCAAAACAAGUCAUUGGGGGUGUGGGAAUAAAAUCAACCUUUGCUUGUAAUUAAAGUUGCUGCUAUUUCUGUAAUGUGUAUUUUUCUCCCCUUGGUAAAGGGCAAUAAAACCAUUACACAAA